AAGCAAGAGCUAGGAAGGCUGGGGGCUGAUUCCAUGCUGCACAAAGACCUGGGAUAUAUACUCAGGGUAGAUUCCAUCAUUCUCACUGUUCAGGUGAGGAAACUGAGGCUCCCCAGAUUUAUGUCAUUUGCUGAAGAUGAGAGUCCUUCCUUCCCUCCUGAUGUGUGACUUCAGCUGUCAUUCAUUAUCCAUCCCCAAACGCCCACCCAUGUUUUCAUAUUGAGUUUGAUGGAGUCUCCUCACCAGCUCGCUGGCCUGACUCUCUGAGUAUUCAGUGUUUAUAUUUCCAUCCUUCACACCCCAGACUCUCUCUCCAUCACCCAUAGAGAGGUCUGGGAAGCUCCUGGUAAAAGCACCAGACUCAAGCCACACCCCACAUCCCCCUGGGAGGUGGCAGGAAACACUUUCCUAAUCAGAGAGGACAGUCUGAUUCUGGGCCUCUGGACGGUUGCAUUCUGAUUCCUUGAGCGACCCUGGCCACCUUAGUACCCACUGACUCUGGGGAUAGGGGAAGGAUAGAAGACCAGACAAAGCCAGCCAAGUGUCGGGAAGCAUCUGGUGGCCCUGGGUGGCUUCUUUUCUGCUAGGAGGGAAACAUGUUUCCAAAAUUUGGACAUAGUGUUGUGAUAAAGAUGAAAACAAUAGACAGUUGGUUCCAAGGACAAUUGACUCAGAAUUCUUGUCUCAAUAAGAUCAUAUUCACCAAAAUGAGGCUUAUCCAUCAUUGCUUUUACCCUAAUUCUGCUUCUUAAACCAAAUGAGGCCAAAUGAUGAUGUUAAGACUGGAUGCUCUUUCGAAGAAAUGCAUAAGGAGUCCUGUCGAGCGUGAUAAAAAAACCCAGAGUCAACCUAGGGAAGUAAGUUAAGGAGCCCUCUAGUUUAUCUAGGAUUGACCUGGGGCUGGAACCCAGAUUCCUGAGCUCUGACUCCGACAUUCCUGUCUCCUCUACUCACCCCUAGAAUCUAUUCCUUUUAGAAGAAAGCUUGGAGUCAGCCACAAGAACCUUACCCAGUCACUAAAGGCUUAAGAAAGAAUGAUCAGGAACUGGGGGAAUUUGCUAAUAAUAACAAAAGAAUGAGAGGGGUGCACUCAGGGCAGGGGGCUUGAAGAACGGCUCCUCUGUUUACGACACACUCAACAGGGGUGUGAGGUCACAGUGAUGAGAGGCCCAAACUUGUGGCCUCCCCGUGAACAAAUGCCCUACACAUCUCCCCUGCAGGAUCAAUGGGACAGGGCUCAAUAUUGGGAGGAAGGCUGUAGUAUUUACUUGGCAAGCCUGCUGUCUACAGCCUGCCCAGUUUAUGCACGGGUAGGCCACAGUUGGUCUUAGAAAUAAAGGCUUUGGAAAAUUAAAAAAAAGAAAGAAUGAGAGUUUCCCAUGCUGGGAAAGCUUCUGUUCUGAAAGCUUCCAGGCUGUUAUCAGUGCUGAUAGGCGACACAGCCGGAGCACGUGGGAGAAGUCAGAAGAGGUGGUGUGUGCCCAGAGCAGCGAGGCGCCACCCACUGCCCUCUUCUCCCCUGGGUUCAGCUGGGGGCCUUACGGAACUCCAGGGUGCUGGAGGCCCCGUUGGUCUCCAUUUGCAGGUGUCUCGCUCAGCGCAGCUGCCCAGAGCCCUGUGUCCUGAGUGAUUUCCAGUAGAUUAGCAGCUCUGGGUCUAAGCUUUUAAGAAAAAAAAAAAAUUGCACUACCCUUCAGUAGGGGCAGCAUUCACAUCUCACACCCAGGCAGAAGCAGAAACGGCCAGGAAUCCACCCCACUUUCUGGGCCUGACAAGGCCACAGUUUGAGAACGUUCAGCACAGGCCAAGCAUCAGAUGGAUUUUGAACAUCUCUGGCUCCUACCAUUUCUGCCUCCACCAUCCCUUUACUCACUGUGCAAGCUACAAAAGCUGAGGGGACAGGAACAAGGAUGAUUUCUGAUGGCAUAUUUAGAGGUGUGCCUGGGAAGUUUGAGCUGCAGCAGUGGAACCUUAAUGCCCAGGAUGAUCCUGUCUAACACCACAGCGGUGACGCCCUUUCUGACCAAGCUGUGGCAGGAGACAGUUCAGCAGGGUGGCAACAUGUCGGGCCUGGCCCGCAGGUCCCCCCGCAGCGGUGACGGCAAGCUGGAGGCCCUCUACGUCCUCAUGGUACUGGGAUUCUUCGGCUUCUUCACCCUGGGCAUCAUGCUGAGCUACAUCCGCUCCAAGAAGCUGGAGCACUCGAACGACCCAUUCAACGUCUACAUCGAGUCCAAUGCCUGGCAAGAGAAGGACAAGGCCUAUGUCCAGGCCCGGGUCCUGGAGAGCUACAGGUCGUGCUAUGUCGUUGAAAACCAUCUGGCCAUAGAACAACCCAACACACACCUUCCUGAGACGAAGCCUUCCCCAUGAACCCCACCACUGGCUAAAACUGGACACAUCCUGCCUGGCAACCUGAUUUUCUAAUCACAUUCCUCUCAUACUCUUUAUUGUGAUGGAUACCACUGGAUUUCUUUUUGGCUGUUGUAAGGGGUGGGGGGUGGAUUAAUGACACUGUUUCACUGUUUCUCUAAAAUCACGUUCUUUUGUGAUAGACUGUCAGUGGUUCCCCCAUAUCUGUCCCUGCCUUGCUAAAUUUAGCAGAAUCCCUGAGGACAUGGCCUCUGAGAAUAGCAGCUGCAUUUCCCAGACUCCCUUGCAGCUAGCAAGGUUGUGUGACUAAGCCCUGGCCAGUAGGCAUGGAAGUGAAGACUGUAAUGUCCAAGUAAUCCUUGGAAAGAAAAGAACGUGCCCUUAACUAACUUUGUCCUGCUUCCCAGUGGCUGGAUGUGGAGGAGGUGGAGAGCAGUUAUGAGACUGGGAAAGAAUGGGGCACUCAAAGAGCCACACACAUCUGGGCCUGGGCGACGUGGAUCCUCCUUACCACCCACCAGGCCAGAUUUACAGGAGAGAGAAAUCCACUCCACUCUUCCUUAAGCCACUGUUAUUCUGAUCUCUGUUAAGGUCGCAGAAUCAAUGCCCUUACUGAUACACCUACCUUAUAGGACUGAACCUAAAGGCAUGACAUUUCCAUACUUGUCACAAGCACACACUGAUUCUGCCCUUGUCACUUCUGUGCUCACUCUUGUGGCUCUAUCCUCCUCCUGCCCUUCCGCCUUCCACUCCUCCCUUGCACCCAUCCUGCACACAUCUCCCUGAAAACACACAGGCACAUACACUCAUAUACAUAGACACACAUACACACCUCAAUCUAGAAAGAACUUGCUUUGUACAGGGCUGAGAUGGAGGAGAAAAAAAUGCCCCCUUCAGAAUGCAUACCAAGGGGAAGGUGCUCGGUCACUGUGGGAGCAGGGAAAGGUGCCCCCACUCCCCGAGAGCCAGGGGAAGGAGUGGCUCUGGGCAGAGAGGGACACAUAGCACUGGGGUGGCAGGUCCUUUUGAGGUGAUGGGCCGGUUUUGUGAGAUGAAUUGUAUCCCCCAAAAAGACAGGUACCUUCAAUGUGACCUAAUUGGGAAAUAGAGUCUUUGCAGAUGAUCUAGUUGAGAUGAGGUCAUUGGGGUGGGCCCUCACCCAAUAUGACUGGAGUCCUUAUCGGAAGAGGGAAAUUCAGACACAGAUGCAUAGGGAGGGCACCAUGCCGUGACAGAGGCAGAGGGUGCAGUGACACAGCCACAAACCAAGGAAGGCCGAGGAUGGAUGCGCAUCCCCAUCCCAAGAAGUCGGGAAGAAGCCAGGAAGGCUCCUCUCCCACAGGUUUCAGAGGAAGCACAGCCCUGCUUGAAUUCAAACUUUUGGCCUCCAGAACUGUGAGUCAGUACCUGUUGUUGAAGCCACCCAGCUUAGGAUACUCUGGCAGCCUACUGCCAUACAGUAUUGGGAUACUAUAGUGAGCCCAUGCAGCACCUCUCACCCACCCAGAGAUGGAGCUGCUCUGCCUUCCAGCGGGGCACCCGGAGGGGCUGCCCCAGCAGAUAGAGAGGGCCUCCGUUCUGCCACCUGCCUUGAAAGGGUCUCCAGCUGCCAUAUGUAGCAUUGGAGUCCUCUGCAAUGCGACAUCCUGAAAGCUCAGCUGCCUGGGCAUUCCUGAAGAGUAUGGAAUAUUUAAAUGAAACAUAUUUUUUUAAAACCUGCGCAUAAGAUAAAAGCAGCCCGUGUGCAUCUUGGGCCAUCCUCAAAUGGACAGACUUGGUCUUGUGAGGUUCCAGUCCUUGUUUCACAUAAUAAACACUGGCAUGGCUCAGCCCCUGAGUUACCACAGUCCUUGAGAUGAGUGGUUCUUUGGGUUACAAAGUCCUCUGAAAGUCUAGUGAGAGCUGUGAUCUUUGCCCCACCCGAAUAAUGCAUAUGGACACCACACCUUGCCUGCCGUGUCCAGGAUUCAUGACCAGUAGCAGCCCAGCUAUGCCUGCCACGUCUCACGGCCCCUGUGUAAGCCAGACCCUUCUUAGGCAGUUGCAUAUUCCCAGACUGAGGCAGGGCAGGUUUGCAGAGAGAGACCCAGAGUGCACGUGACCCGCAGUGUGAUCCCUGGCACGCACUGACUUUGAUAUUCCAGGCACACGGACUGGCUAUUUAUCACCACUUCUUUUUCCCCACUAAGAUUCCUGUGCCUUUUAAGGCAGAGGGAGAUCCCUAUGGCGUUAGUCUUCCCAGGCCUUAAAGGGCCCUUGUCUUCACUCACAAACCUCUUAUCUCUUCUUCUCCUUCCUCUACAUUUUAAAGGGGGAGAGGGAAAAGUAACCGGGAGACAAAUUGAGCCACAUAUUUUCAGACACUUGUUACCAUAUUUUAAAAUCUGGCUUCACAUACACAGAGUCUUUGCUAUGCACCAUGUACUGUUCUAAGCUUCUUAAAAAUAGAAUCUCAAUUAUUAUUUUGCAGGCAAUACUCUGUGCAUUCAUUAGCUAGGACAACAAUGCAUUUGCAGUAGUGAGAUUUCGUUAAAAAAUUAAAGCCAUUUACUAUGA